GGCCUAGCUACUUGGGAGGCUGAGGCAGGAGGAUCACUUCUGCCCAGGAGUUCAGUGUUACAGUGAGCUAUGGUUUUAGCAGUGUACGCCAGCGUCGGUGACAGAGUGAGGCCCUGUUUCUAGAAAAAUAACUGCUGUGCUUUGCCUGGGCCUCCUGGAAAGCAGGUGGUCUGAGCAUCACCUCAGUCAGGGAGGUGCUUAUGGGACCUGAGCAGUGGGAGAGUCUUGGAGUGAUCUCUGUUGUGAUCAAGGGGCGGUGGAGUUGUGUGUAUUUCAGGAAGUCUUACUGUGAAUUUUCCCUUUCCCAGACACUUCAUCCCUAAAGGCAUCAGGCAGGGCAUAGCAGGCCUGGGGAGUGGCUGUGGCCUGAGCCAGAGUCCCAGCCCAAGCAGGGAGAGGUGGCCAGCAUGCCUGGGCCCAGCGUGACGCUGAUACUUCAGUGAGAAGGGAGGGCACUUAGGGACAUACACGGGUGAAAGAAUUAAUCAAGGCUGCAGGAAGCCUUGGUAUUUUGCUGUCAAGGAGUCAGCGGCCUGGCAGAAGGGAUAAAGGAGAGUGACCCCUGUGGGCUGGCUCAGGAUUGGAAUGCUGACGCAAACCCCUGGGUUUCAGUGUGUCGGCAGGCAUGGAUAACCAUGGGUCUUGCCGUAAGUUUCUAGCUUUGUUCACCGCAGGGUCCUGGGAACAGUAACGCCCCAGUAACACUGAGCACACCUAGUGUUCAGAUGUUGUCUUCUAAAAACCGUUUUCCACUAAAAUGACAAGGACUCCUGAGAGAAAAGGCUGAUUGCGGGACUGGGAUAAGGAAAUACAAGAUGAGCGGAGACCGUCCUGUGUCAGAGAGCAGUGGACAUGGGCAUGACGUGGACGUGGAUGUCAGCAGAGCAGCCUCCCUCCCAUGGCCGGGUCCUUCAGCUGGAGCCCUAAGCUGUGCAGCCCAGCCACAGCCCGUGACCACCAGGGAUGCCAAGACCCUGAGUGAGCACCUGGAGCCCAUAGGAGGACUGGGCAUGAGAACUGCUGUAGAGCUCUUCCCCGAGACACAACGACCCCAGGAGACGCCAGGCAGGCCCCCGGCCUCACGUUCAAAGCCCACUGCUGGAGGCGGCAAGUGGAGGCUGCGUGCAUGUGGAAUUCCCGGCAGGACUCUUAGCUCACAUCUCCUCACGAGGGGGCCGAAGUCAGCCUGGAAGAGGACGUCCUGCACACAGCUGGCCUGUGCCUUCCAGGUGUCAGGGGCAGCCCAGGAGUCAGGAGAGGCUGAGGAACCUUCCAGCUUGAGGAGCCGGACAAGACGUGGCAGCUGGGAUUGGGAUGCAGACUGUCCUGCAGGGAGAGGCGCUGCUGGGACCGGGUCCUACGGGGGAGGGCCUGGGGAGGGGCCAUUCAUCAUGGCCCGGUCUCAAUGGCAUCCUGCUUCUGGAGGGGAUGCCCUUGUCUGUAGGAAACACGUGCAGAAUGUUCCGGGUGGAGGAAAGUCAGAACAAUCGAGCUUUCCAGGAAAGCAGCGAGGCACCCUCUCUGCUGUGGCAGAUGCAGCAGGUGCAGGUGCGGGGAGGACAGAGGCCUGGCCUCCUCACGGCCCUGCCUUCCACGUGGGGUUUCCUGCCCUUACCACCCCAGCCCACCUCCCGAUGAAUUCCUUGUACAGUUAAAGUGAUCUUCCCUUCUUUC